GACACCGCACGCUGAGCUCUGUGAUGUAGCCGCUUGCGGAGACUGCAAGCAGCCGCGGCGCGCCCGGCCCUCCCUCUUCCGCUGCCGCCGUGGGAAUGGAAACAUCUGCCCCACGUGCCGGAAGCCAAGUGGUGGCGACAACUGCGCGCCACUCCGCGGCCUACCGCGCAGAUCCUCUACGUGUGUCCUCGCGAGACAAGCUCACCGAAAUGGCCGCGUCCAGUCAAGGAAACUUUGAGGGAAAUUUUGAGUCACUGGACCUUGCGGAAUUUGCUAAGAAGCAGCCAUGGUGGCGUAAGCUGUUCGGGCAGGAAUCUGGACCUUCAGCAGAAAAGUAUAGCGUGGCAACCCAGCUGUUCAUUGGAGGUGUCACUGGAUGGUGCACAGGUUUCAUAUUCCAGAAGGUUGGAAAGUUGGCUGCAACAGCUGUGGGAGGUGGAUUUUUUCUCCUUCAGCUUGCAAACCAUACUGGGUACAUCAAAGUUGACUGGCAACGAGUGGAGAAGGACAUGAAGAAAGCCAAAGAGCAGCUGAAGAUCCGUAAGAGCAAUCAGAUACCUACUGAGGUCAGGAGCAAAGCUGAGGAGGUGGUGUCAUUUGUGAAGAAGAAUGUUCUAGUAACUGGGGGAUUUUUCGGAGGCUUUCUGCUUGGCAUGGCAUCCUAAGGAAGAUGACCUCAUGUUCAUUGUUCCUGGUUUUUUCCAGCCAGCAGCCUCUACACUCCAUCAUAGGACAUCGAGUCCCUCCUCCUCUUCUCCCAUGCCUUCUUCCCUGCCAUGGCAAAUCUGAGUGGCUUCUCUAAGCAUCUGCUGGUACAAGUCAAUGUGGCACCAUGAGCUUCAUGGUGGCAGAAGAGACAAUAGUCCUUAGCUCUCCUCCCAGUACACCCCCUACUUGGCCAGUCUGUAGGCCAACAAGAAGGUUCCUUUACCCCCAUGCAAGACACUUAUGAGAACACAUUACAAGAUGGCUGACCGUGGAGGAUGAGUGGAUCCUGAAAGGUUGUCCCAAACUGUUGAUUUGGAAAAGAAAUAAGCACAUAGAUAACCUUAUUGUGUGCUGCAUGGAAAGGAACUGAAUACAUUUGCCUUUAAGCAUGAAAGAUUUUGGUAUCUUGGUGUCUACUUUCUUUUUUAGUUGGUUUUACAUUACAGAAAGCUAUUUAAAUGUGUUAUAAUUAUGCCGACAAAAUUGGCAGCAUAAUUACUGUAAUUGAAAAAUCUGAUAUUGUCCAGGAAUGCUUUCUACCGUACAGGAUAAUGUAUCUCAUGGCUGUUUCCAAAGGGUUUAUUUAUUGUAAAACAAGUGAUUUAGGUGGGAAAGGGAAGAUUUUGGAUUUUUAUUUUGUAGAAAAGGUUUUAAGCUUUGAAAUGUGAAUGAAAUAUCCUUAUCAAAACAUUAGGGGUGGCCAUAACUCCUCUGUGCCACUUCUACUAUUUUUUUUUUUAAUCUAGUUAGUAUGAAAUACAACAUUUAAACCGGAAUUUUAAAGAAGUAGCUUUCCAGGGAUUCAGAAUUAAGAAAGAUAGUGAUAGGACAUGAGAAAUAAAUUUCCAUCAAGUGUAAUCUACCGUCUCAUGAUGACCACAACCCUGAGAAUUAUUCUUUAAAAGCUUACACACACACACACACACGGGCACACACGCACACACAGAAUCUUACCACAUUUUGCUGUAGUGGCAUGUUACCAUGUCUACAGUCCCUACUAGAAUAUCAGUCAGCUUUCAGAGGGCAAGACUUCUGUCUUCACCAUUAUACUCACAGGGCCUAGCACUUAAUAGGUGCUGAGUAUUUGAAUAAUGACUUUAUAGAAAGAAAACUCACUAUUAAAGGUUAGUUUUACUCAGAAUUGUUAAUCUUGGAGAUGAUCUCUUGUGAAAUAUGAGUGUGUUUCUAAGGCCAUACAUUUAAAAAUGUUUGCAUUUUAACCCGUCUUGAGAAUGAUGUAUUGAAUUUGAAAAUCAAAACUACCAGUGGAUGUGUGGAACUUUACAGAAACCACCUAUUUGCGUUUUUCUCCUUACAUUUAAGGAAACAUAAGCCAUUUUGCUUGCAAUAUGUAUGAAUCAUCUCAAAACCAUAAUGGUAUGAGCCUCUUUGCUGCAUAUUUUGCUAUAAGAACUUAUUUUUUUUCACUUUUUAUUAUGGACGCUUUCAGGAAUAUAUAAAAGUAGAGAAUAUAGUACAAUAAUCCCCCUGUGUAUCUAUCACUCACUCACAACAAUCAUCAAAUUAUAGCUCUGCUGGUUUUUACCAGUUAUUGUGAAACAAAUAUCAAAAUGUCAUUUUAUCAUAUUUCAGUAUGUAUCUCUAAAAGGUAAGAAUUAUUUCUAAAAAUCAUAAAUACCUCAUCAUAUCAGACAUUAACAGUAAUUACAUAAUAUCCAAAAUCUGAUCAGUGUUCAAAAUUUCCUCAAGUGUUUUAUAUUUAGUUUGUUUGAAUCAAAAUUCAUGCAAGGUUCACAUCGUAUUUGCAUGAUUUGGAUAAGUCUCUUAACCUUAUAGAUCCUCCUCUAUUUUUUUUUUUUUGCUUGCUAUAUAUUUAUAUCUCUAUAUAUAUUGAUAUAGACAUAUGUAGUGACACUGAGUCAUCUGUUUCCUGCUUCCCCACACUCUGCCUCUCCUGACAUCUGGGUCUCUGGGUUAUGCCAUAUAUGGUGAUAGUGGCUGCAGCCACUUUACCUGUGUGACUUACCCACAGCAAUGGGAUGGUAACAGCAAAGCUAACCAAAGUGCUCUGUGCCCCUUUGGGUUGCAUGUGGGGAGACUGGCCACCCAAUGCCUCUCCAGUGGGGUAGGGGUUGUCUUUUGGUGCAUCUGUUUUUCCUGUGAUUAUUGGUGAGGGCAGCAAAGAUUAGCAGGUGGUUGUAAACUACCUUGAGUAGGUUGUAAUAAAUAGUCUGGCCUCAGACUGUAUUCUGAUUGUCUGAAUUAAGAUCUGUAGGUAGGUCCCUCCUGAAGUUUUUUCCCAGCUGGCUGCCUCUACGACUGUGAGGGUCAUGGUUGAGGUCAGUAUUGCAGGUUGGCCUCAUCCUGCUAGUAUGAGAACGGCUGUGAGUUCUGCCCACGGUGUGAGGCCACUGUGACCACUUGGGAUUGUGCAGAGCUGGCAUGGAGGUUGAACACGCACAGCUGCACACCUUGUUUUCAGUUUAGCUGAACCAUCGGUGAAGGAGGCUCAGGCAUUUGGGGUUACCUGUGAAUCAAGGCCCUAUUGUGCCAGCAGUUUUGUUUCAGGUGGUGAAGUGGGAGUUAAGGUUUCCCCCAAAAGAACAGCUGCCACUCCUCCAUGCAAAACCGAGAUGAUUCAAGGACCAGGCAGCUCCACCUUUCAGUGCACUACUUUCAUUUGACUGGAGAGGCCUGCUUAGCUAGGCACGUAUUUUCUCCAGUAGCAGAGUCCAAUGACGCUCUGGACUUCCUAAUUAGUGGUGGUGGGGCGGAAGUUUUUCCUUGGGAAGAGCGUUGUCGCUGUAUAUGGUCCGCAGAAACUUGACUUGGAAUGUGUUCGGGGUUUCAUCGCCCCCUUGUGGCGGCGACGUGGUAACACCGCACUCAAGGCUUCCAACUUGUCAACCAAUAGGAUGGCAUCUACGUAGUGAAGGCUUCCCUUCCCUUGUCCUGCAGCGUGCUGGACAGUGUCCCGGCUCAGGGACCCCUUCUGUCCCCUUCCUGGCUACUAUGGGUCGGCCCUGCGUCCUCACCACUUUGAGCCACCCUUUGACCCAGCGUCUCUCCCGCAAUGGGACCUGGUGGGAUGGGGACUUGGAGCAUGCUACAGGAGAGGUAGAACUUUUGAGUCUCUUCUUCCCAAGGUUCUCCCCAGAGUCGGAGAGCAGAGACGGAUCCAGGGGCACUUUCUGGCCGCUGCCUGCUCGGGCUCAACAGAUGGAGUCCAAUGUUUCAGUCUCCCCCAAGAAUGUGUAUCCUCAUUGCUGACACGGGAGCUGGGUGCGGGGAGAGAUGUGGUGGUGGGGACCCUUGCCUGAGCAGCCCAUUGUCAUGAGUGUUAUUGCCAUUGUGAUAAUAUGUUAGCAUGACUCUCCUCCCAAAUGGCCGCUUGUUUGUUGCAAUCUCCCGCCACUCAGCCUCCAGACAUUCAUUAACAGGACAGUGGGGUUCUUGACUCCCCUACCACUGGGGUGACAGUCCUUGCUACUGGAUCUGGGCAGUUACUGUCUCAUGGAUGCUGGCAGAAGACGAUUCAAGUUGGCGGACUAGAUUCUACAAGGAAUGAUCUCUUGCAUAAUUCUAGCCAACAUGCUCUUGGGGUGGGUGCUUCUGGUUUUGGAAAGCAAAGUUACUGUGUAGUUAACAACUAUUGUGGUAAGAAUAGUCUCUCCAUCAUUCUUUUGUUUCACGGUUGUCAGAAAGAUGGGCAUAACUAAUGGUUGGGCUCUUAUUUGGAACCUCUACUUUUGUACAGUUUGGGAAUCUCUGCUUGAAAAGAUGGUAUACUGAUGGAUUUGAAAUUUCUGAGUAUCAUCAAUGUUUCAUGAUGAUCUCAAUUUCUUCUCAGAGGGAAGCUCACAGCCAGUUUUGGACCCCAGAGAAAAAUGUGGCUGCUGCCCUCUACUCCCUCUACCAAAUUAUCAGCUUCAUUUCUUUGUCAUGAAAUCUAGUAUGAUUUCUCAGAAAUCAGGCCCAGAACUAAAAUACAUUUUCUGCCCAAUUUUCUAAGAGGUCACACUAACAUCUGAGUAAUUGGGCAGAAAACCUAUUUUAGUUCUGAGCCUGAUUUUUCUAGAAGUCAUAUGGUAUAGCUUAUAUUUCCGAUGCUUGCAUUCUUUUUAAGGGGUCAUGAAUCUUAAUACUUUUUUUUUUAAAAGAAAAGUGUCGCACUUUUUCACAUUUUUAUAAAGCUUUAAAGUCAGUUUACUGACUUUUCAAAAGUGUCUACCUUUUUAAAUUUUAAAAUGGUAAGAAAUGACAUUCCUGAGAGCAGUGGCUUUCAUCCUUGCUUGCACUUGGGAAUCACCUGUGAAAUUUUAAAAACUACUAAUGCCUGGCUCUCAUCCUAGAGAUUCUGAUUUCACUGGUCUGGAGUGCUGUUCAGGCAUCCUGAGGUUUUAAAGUGUCUUAGCUUUUUCUAAUGAGCAGCAGAGACUGAGAACCACUGAAGUACACAGUUGGAAGCUGGUGCUGAAAAAAUUAAGAGUUUUGCUGUUAACUCCUUAAGAGGGCUUUAAAGCCUUUUAUAUUAAGUGCCAUACAACUUCAGAUGCCUUCUGAAUACUGAACACAAGUGUAAUAUUAUAGUUCAUUAAAUGUCUUAGGAAUCGUGUGGAGUGAAUGCAAGGAAAGGAGUGACAAGAUAUCACCCCACAAAUGACUUACCCAUUACGAAGGGAAAACUACCUUUCUAGCUAAAAGGUCUGUCAGUCACUAACCAAGUGAUUAAACUUAGCAUCACUAAUAGCCAACUUAACAAAGUUUUUUUUUUUUUUUGGUUUCUAAAAUGGGAGAUCAUAGUUUUCACCUUCCUAGAGUUCUUUGCUUAAGACUGAGAUUCAGUGUUACUCUUGGUCCCUAACAAUAAGAAGCACUCAGUAAAUGUUAAGCCUUCUAUGAUGGCUAUUUUAUUUUUUUGUAUGUCAUAAUAAUACCUAAGAAUAAGAAGAGUUAAAUUAAUGUCUUCAAAUGGAUUUGUUGACUUAAACUGACACAAUCCUUUAAAAGAAGGAACUGAUUUGAACCUUUCAAAACUGAAAGAAAGUCGUAUACUGAUACAGUUUGGAGCCACCGAAUGUCAUGUUGAACCGUAUUCCCUAAUGGAGGUGGAUCCUGGUGAGAGGUGAUUGGAUCGUGGGGGCCAUCCCCUCUUGGUACUUCACUCAUGAUAGUGAGUUCUCAUGAGAUCUGGCACUUCACCCCUCACUCUCUCUUGCUCCUGCUUUGGCCAUGUGGAGUGCUCACUCCCCUUUUGCUUUCUGCCAUGGCUGUAAGUUUCCUGAGGCGUCCCCAGAAGCCCAUCAGAUACCAGUGCCAUGCUUCCUGUACAGCCCAUGGAACUGUGAGCCAACUAAACCUCUUUUAUUUAUAAAUUACCGAGUCUCAGGCACUUUUUAUAGCAAUGCAACAAUGGACUAAUACAUAUACUUUAGCAUAAAAACAUUUAAAAGAGUCUGAAACUGGAGUAGUUAACUCAGUAAAAAUAACUUGGCAAUAAAACACAGAAAAACAAUCUAUUUGAUCAUGUAGUGAUUCCUAAUGUAAAUCCUAGUACAACUGUCAACUGAUAAUUUUAAAUGUAAUUUAGAUUUGUAGAUGGUGUAACAUUAAAGUUGUAUGAUGUUU